GCUGUCCCGAGCUGGCCGGCGAGCGGGCGGCUGCGGGCGGCGCGGAGCGGGCGGCGCGGAGCGAGCGAGCGAGAGAGCGGCGCGGGCCGGGCCAUGGGGUGGCGGGCGGCGGGCGCGCUGCUGCUGGCGCUGCUGCUGCACGGGCGGCUGCUGGCGGUGACCCAUGGGCUGAGGGCAUACGAUGGCUUGUCUCUGCCUGAGGACAUAGAGACCGUCACAGCAAGCCAAAUGCGCUGGACACAUUCGUACCUUUCUGAUGAUGAGGACAUGCUGGCUGACAGCAUCUCAGGAGACGACCUGGGCAGUGGGGACCUGGGCAGCGGGGACUUCCAGAUGGUUUAUUUCCGAGCCCUGGUGAAUUUCACUCGCUCCAUCGAGUACAGCCCUCAGCUGGAGGAUGCAGGCUCCAGAGAGUUCCGAGAGGUGUCCGAGGCUGUGGUAGACACGCUGGAGUCGGAGUACUUGAAAAUUCCCGGAGACCAGGUUGUCAGUGUGGUGUUCAUCAAGGAGCUGGAUGGCUGGGUUUUUGUGGAGCUGGAUGUGGGCUCGGAAGGGAAUGCGGAUGGGGCUCAGAUUCAGGAGAUGCUGCUCAGGGUCAUCUCCAGCGGCUCUGUGGCCUCCUACGUCACCUCUCCCCAGGGAUUCCAGUUCCGACGCCUGGGCACAGCACAGACCCCCCCACCCCCGCCGGCCGCUGUGGCGGUCGCAGUGACACCAGUGCCCCAGUUCCCAAGAGCCUGCACGGAGGCCGAGUUUGCCUGCCACAGCUACAAUGAGUGUGUGGCCCUGGAGUAUCGCUGUGACCGGCGGCCCGACUGCAGGGACAUGUCUGAUGAGCUCAAUUGUGAGGAGCCAGUCCUGGGUAUCAGCCCCACAUUCUCUCUCCUUGUGGAGACGACAUCUUUACCGCCCCGGCCAGAGACAACCAUCAUGCGACAGCCACCAGUCACCCACGCUCCUCAGCCCCUGCUUCCCGGUUCCGUCAGGCCCCUGCCCUGUGGGCCCCAGGAGGCCGCAUGCCGCAAUGGGCACUGCAUCCCCAGAGACUACCUCUGCGACGGACAGGAGGACUGCGAGGACGGCAGCGAUGAGCUAGACUGUGGCCCCCCGCCACCCUGUGAGCCCAACGAGUUCCCCUGCGGGAAUGGACAUUGUGCCCUCAAGCUGUGGCGCUGCGAUGGUGACUUUGACUGUGAGGACCGAACUGAUGAAGCCAACUGCCCCACCAAGCGUCCUGAGGAAGUGUGCGGGCCCACACAGUUCCGAUGCGUCUCUACCAACAUGUGCAUCCCAGCCAGCUUCCACUGUGACGAGGAGAGCGACUGUCCUGACCGGAGCGACGAGUUUGGCUGCAUGCCCCCCCAGGUGGUGACACCUCCCCGGGAGUCCAUCCAGGCUUCCCGGGGCCAGACAGUGACCUUCACCUGCGUGGCCAUUGGCGUCCCCACCCCCAUCAUCAAUUGGAGGCUCAACUGGGGCCACAUCCCCUCUCAUCCCAGGGUGACAGUGACCAGCGAGGGUGGCCGUGGCACACUGAUCAUCCGUGAUGUGAAGGAGUCAGACCAGGGUGCCUACACCUGUGAGGCCAUGAACGCCCGGGGCAUGGUGUUUGGCAUUCCUGACGGUGUCCUUGAGCUCGUCCCACAACGAGCAGGCCCCUGCCCUGACGGCCACUUCUACCUGGAGCACAGCGCCGCCUGCCUGCCCUGCUUCUGCUUUGGCAUCACCAGCGUGUGCCAGAGCACCCGCCGCUUCCGGGACCAGAUCAGGCUGCGCUUUGACCAACCCGAUGACUUCAAGGGUGUGAAUGUGACAAUGCCUGCGCAGCCCGGCACGCCACCCCUCUCCUCCACGCAGCUGCAGAUCGACCCAUCCCUGCACGAGUUCCAGCUAGUCGACCUGUCCCGCCGCUUCCUCGUCCACGACUCCUUCUGGGCUCUGCCUGAACAGUUCCUGGGCAACAAGGUGGACUCCUAUGGCGGCUCCCUGCGUUACAACGUGCGCUACGAGUUGGCCCGUGGCAUGCUGGAGCCAGUGCAGCGGCCGGACGUGGUCCUCAUGGGUGCCGGGUACCGCCUCCUCUCCCGAGGCCACACACCCACCCAACCUGGUGCUCUGAACCAGCGCCAGGUCCAGUUCUCUGAGGAGCACUGGGUCCAUGAGUCUGGCCGGCCGGUGCAGCGCGCGGAGCUGCUGCAGGUGCUGCAGAGCCUGGAGGCCGUGCUCAUCCAGACCGUGUACAACACCAAGAUGGCCAGCGUGGGACUUAGCGACAUCGCCAUGGAUACCACCGUCACCCAUGCCACCAGCCAUGGCCGUGCCCACAGUGUGGAGGAGUGCAGAUGCCCCAUUGGCUAUUCUGGCUUGUCCUGCGAGAGCUGUGAUGCCCACUUCACUCGGGUGCCUGGUGGGCCCUACCUGGGCACCUGCUCUGGUUGCAAUUGCAAUGGCCAUGCCAGCUCCUGUGACCCUGUGUAUGGCCACUGCCUGAAUUGCCAGCACAACACGGAGGGGCCACAGUGCAACAAGUGCAAGGCUGGCUUCUUUGGGGACGCCAUGAAGGCCACGGCCACUUCCUGCCGGCCCUGCCCUUGCCCAUACAUCGAUGCCUCCCGCAGAUUCUCAGACACUUGCUUCCUGGACACGGAUGGCCAAGCCACAUGUGACGCCUGUGCCCCAGGCUACACUGGCCGCCGCUGUGAGAGCUGUGCCCCCGGAUACGAGGGCAACCCCAUCCAGCCCGGCGGGAAGUGCAGGCCCGUCAACCAGGAGAUUGUGCGCUGUGACGAGCGUGGCAGCAUGGGGACCUCCGGGGAGGCCUGCCGCUGUAAGAACAAUGUGGUGGGGCGCUUGUGCAAUGAAUGUGCUGACGGCUCUUUCCACCUGAGUACCCGAAACCCCGAUGGCUGCCUCAAGUGCUUCUGCAUGGGUGUCAGUCGCCACUGCACCAGCUCUUCAUGGAGCCGUGCCCAGUUGCAUGGGGCCUCUGAGGAGCCUGGUCACUUCAGCCUGACCAACGCCGCAAGCACCCACACCACCAACGAGGGCAUCUUCUCCCCCACGCCCGGGGAACUGGGAUUCUCCUCCUUCCACAGACUCUUAUCUGGACCCUACUUCUGGAGCCUCCCUUCACGCUUCCUGGGGGACAAGGUGACCUCCUAUGGAGGAGAGCUGCGCUUCACAGUGACCCAGAGGUCCCAGCCGGGCUCCACACCCCUGCACGGGCAGCCGUUGGUGGUGCUGCAAGGUAACAACAUCAUCCUAGAGCACCAUGUGGCCCAGGAGCCCAGCCCCGGCCAGCCCAGCACCUUCAUUGUGCCUUUCCGGGAGCAAGCAUGGCAGCGGCCCGAUGGGCAGCCAGCCACACGGGAGCACCUGCUGAUGGCACUGGCAGGCAUCGACACCCUCCUGAUCCGAGCAUCCUACGCCCAGCAGCCCGCUGAGAGCAGGGUCUCUGGCAUCAGCAUGGACGUGGCUGUGCCCGAGGAAACCGGCCAGGACCCCGCGCUGGAAGUGGAACAGUGCUCCUGCCCACCCGGGUACCGUGGGCCGUCCUGCCAGGACUGUGACACAGGCUACACACGCACGCCCAGUGGCCUCUACCUGGGUACCUGUGAACGCUGCAGCUGCCAUGGCCACUCAGAGGCCUGCGAGCCAGAAACAGGUGCCUGCCAGGGCUGCCAGCAUCACACGGAGGGCCCUCGGUGUGAGCAGUGCCAGCCAGGAUACUACGGGGACGCCCAGCGGGGGACACCACAGGACUGCCAGCUGUGCCCCUGCUACGGAGACCCUGCUGCCGGCCAGGCUGCCCACACUUGUUUUCUGGACACAGACGGCCACCCCACCUGUGAUGCGUGCUCCCCAGGCCACAGUGGGCGUCACUGUGAGAGGUGCGCCCCUGGCUACUAUGGCAACCCCAGCCAGGGCCAGCCAUGCCAGAGAGACAGCCAGGUGCCAGGGCCCAUAGGCUGCAACUGUGACCCCCAAGGCAGCGUCAGCAGCCAGUGUGAUGCUGCUGGUCAGUGCCAGUGCAAGGCCCAGGUGGAAGGCCUCACUUGCAGCCACUGCCGGCCCCACCACUUCCACCUGAGUGCCAGCAACCCAGACGGCUGCCUGCCCUGCUUCUGUAUGGGCAUCACCCAGCAGUGCGCCAGCUCUGCCUACACACGCCACCUGAUCUCCACCCACUUUGCCCCUGGGGACUUCCAAGGCUUUGCCCUGGUGAACCCACAGCGAAACAGCCGCCUGACAGGAGAAUUCACUGUGGAACCCGUGCCCGAGGGUGCCCAGCUCUCUUUUGGCAACUUUGCCCAACUCGGCCAUGAGUCCUUCUACUGGCAGCUGCCGGAGACAUACCAGGGAGACAAGGGGGAGGCGUACUUUGCGCGGAUGCGCCGGGCUCACCAGAGGACCCUGCCCAUGGCUCUAGCUCCAGGACUUUGGGAGGUCUUAGCUCGCCUGCUCCCUCCAUUUCAUCAGAACCGCACAUCCCUCUCAGAGGAGCAGUUGCGGGCAGCCGUGACAGCUGGGAGGAUCCCAGAGCCCCCAGAGGGCAGGGACUGGGCACAGCGGGCAUCACAGGUGGACGAGGCUCAGAGACGGAUGGAUGCUGAGAUCUGGCAGCUCCUGUCCAGCUUUGCUGCCCAACCCCAACCCCCUCCCCAGGGGCUCUCUCCUCAUCCCCAGCCUGCAGCUGCUCUGCGAGCAGCACCUCCUCCUUCUUCUUCCUCCUCCUCCUCCUCUUCCUCAGCUUCUCUGUCUUUCUCACCAGGCUCUCAGUUCUCUCUCUCCUACGAAGGCUUCUCUCUGCUUCCUGGAAGCCUCUAUUACUGGCAGCUGCCCCGGGCCUUCCUGGGGGACAAGGUGGCGGCCUACGGUGGGAAGUUGCGAUACACCCUCUCCUACACAGCAGGCCCACAGGGCAGCCCACUCUCUGACCCCGAUGUGCAGAUCACGGGCAACAACAUCAUGCUAGUGGCCUCCCAGCCAGCGCUGCAGGGCCCUGAGAGGAGGAGCUACGAGAUCAUGUUCCGAGAGGAAUUCUGGCGCCGGCCCGAUGGGCAGCCGGCCACACGCGAGCACCUCCUGAUGGCACUGGCCGACCUGGAUGAGCUCCUGAUCCGGGCCACGUUCUCCUCCGUGCCGCUGGCGGCCAGCAUCAGCGCAGUCAGCCUGGAGGUCGCCCAGCCGGGGCCCUCAAACAGACCCCGCGCCCUCGAGGUGGAGGAGUGCCGCUGCCCGCCAGGCUACAUCGGUCUGUCCUGCCAGGACUGUGCCCCCGGCUACACGCGCACCGGGAGUGGGCUCUACCUCGGCCACUGCGAGCUAUGUGAAUGCAAUGGCCACUCAGACCUGUGCCACCCAGAGACUGGGGCCUGCUCGCAAUGCCAGCACAACGCCGCAGGGGAGUUCUGCGAGCUUUGUGCCCCUGGCUACUACGGAGAUGCCACAGCCGGGACGCCUGAGGACUGCCAGCCCUGUGCCUGCCCACUGACCAACCCAGAGAACAUGUUUUCCCGCACCUGUGAGAGCCUGGGAGCCGGCGGGUACCGCUGCACGGCCUGCGAACCCGGCUACACUGGCCAGUACUGUGAGCAGUGUGGCCCAGGUUACGUGGGUAACCCCAGUGUGCAAGGGGGCCAGUGCCUGCCAGAGACAAACCAAGCCCCACUGGUGGUCGAGGUCCAUCCUGCUCGAAGCAUAGUGCCCCAAGGUGGCUCCCACUCCCUGCGGUGUCAGGUCAGUGGGAGCCCACCCCACUACUUCUAUUGGUCCCGUGAGGAUGGGCGGCCUGUGCCCAGCGGCACCCAGCAGCGACAUCAAGGCUCCGAGCUCCACUUCCCCAGCGUCCAGCCCUCGGAUGCUGGGGUCUACAUUUGCACCUGCCGUAAUCUCCACCAAUCCAAUACCAGCCGGGCAGAGCUGCUGGUCACUGAGGCUCCAAGCAAGCCCAUCACAGUGACUGUGGAGGAGCAGCGGAGCCAGAGCGUGCGCCCCGGAGCUGACGUCACCUUCAUCUGCACAGCCAAAAGCAAGUCCCCAGCCUAUACCCUGGUGUGGACCCGCCUGCACAACGGGAAACUGCCCACCCGAGCCAUGGAUUUCAAUGGCAUCCUGACCAUUCGCAACGUCCAGCUGAGUGAUGCAGGCACCUACGUGUGCACCGGCUCCAACAUGUUUGCCAUGGACCAGGGCACAGCCACUCUACAUGUGCAGGCCUCGGGCACCUUGUCCGCCCCCGUGGUCUCCAUCCAUCCGCCACAGCUCACAGUGCAGCCCGGGCAACUGGCGGAGUUCCGCUGCAGCGCCACAGGGAGCCCCACGCCCACCCUCGAGUGGACAGGGGGCCCCGGCGGCCAGCUCCCUGCGAAGGCACAAAUCCACGGCGGCAUCCUGCGCCUGCCAGCUGUCGAGCCCACGGAUCAGGCCCAGUACUUGUGCCGAGCCCACAGCAGCGCUGGGCAGCAGGUGGCCAGGGCUGUGCUCCACGUGCAUGGGGGCGGUGGGCCCAGAGUCCAAGUGAGCCCAGAGAGGACCCAGGUCCACGCAGGCCGCACCGUCAGGCUGUACUGCAGGGCUGCAGGCGUGCCUAGCGCCACCAUCACCUGGAGGAAGGAAGGGGGCAGCCUCCCACCACAGGCCCGGUCAGAGCGCACAGACAUCGCGACACUGCUCAUCCCAGCCAUCACGACUGCUGACGCCGGCUUCUACCUCUGCGUGGCCACCAGCCCUGCAGGCACUGCCCAGGCCCGGAUCCAAGUGGUUGUCCUUUCAGCCUCAGAUGCCAGCCCACCGCCGGUCAAGAUUGAGUCCUCAUCGCCUUCUGUGACAGAAGGGCAAACACUCGACCUCAACUGUGUGGUGGCAGGGUCAGCCCAUGCCCAGGUCACCUGGUACAGGCGAGGGGGUAGCCUGCCUCCCCACACCCAGGUGCACGGCUCCCGUCUGCGGCUCCCCCAGGUCUCACCAGCUGAUUCUGGAGAAUAUGUGUGCCGUGUGGAGAAUGGAUCGGGCCCCAAGGAGGCCUCCAUUACUGUGUCUGUGCUCCACGGCACCCAUUCUGGCCCCAGCUACACCCCAGUGCCCGGCAGCACCCGGCCCAUCCGCAUCGAGCCCUCCUCCUCACACGUGGCGGAAGGGCAGACCCUGGAUCUGAACUGCGUGGUGCCCGGGCAGGCCCACGCCCAGGUCACGUGGCACAAGCGUGGGGGCAGCCUCCCUGCCCGGCACCAGACCCACGGCUCGCUGCUGCGGCUGCACCAGGUGACCCCGGCCGACUCAGGCGAGUAUGUGUGCCAUGUGGUGGGCACCUCCGGCCCCCUAGAGGCCUCAGUCCUGGUCACCAUCGAAGCCUCUGUCAUCCCUGGACCCAUCCCACCUGUCAGGAUCGAGUCUUCAUCCUCCACAGUGGCCGAGGGCCAGACCCUGGAUCUGAGCUGCGUGGUGGCAGGGCAGGCCCACGCCCAGGUCACAUGGUACAAGCGUGGGGGCAGCCUCCCUGCCCGGCACCAGGUUCGUGGCUCCCGCCUGUACAUCUUCCAGGCCUCACCUGCCGAUGCGGGACAGUACGUCUGCCGGGCCAGCAACGGCAUGGAGGCCUCCAUCACGGUCACAGUAACUGGGACCCAGGGGGCCAACUUAGCCUACCCUGCCGGCAGCACCCAGCCCAUCCGCAUCGAGCCCUCCUCCUCGCAAGUGGCGGAAGGGCAGACCCUGGAUCUGAACUGCGUGGUGCCCGGGCAGUCCCAUGCCCAGGUCACGUGGCACAAGCGUGGGGGCAGCCUCCCUGUCCGGCACCAGACCCACGGCUCCCUGCUGAGACUCUACCAAGCGUCCCCCGCCGACUCGGGCGAGUACGUGUGCCGAGUGUUGGGCAGCUCCGUGCCUCUAGAGGCCUCUGUCCUGGUCACCAUUGAGCCUGCGGGCUCAGUGCCUGCACUUGGGGUCACCCCCACGGUCCGGAUCGAGUCAUCGUCUUCGCAAGUGGCCGAGGGGCAGACCCUGGACCUGAACUGCCUCGUUGCUGGUCAGGCCCAUGCCCAGGUCACGUGGCACAAGCGCGGGGGCAGCCUCCCGGCCCGGCACCAGGUGCAUGGCUCGAGGCUACGCCUGCUCCAGGUGACCCCAGCUGAUUCAGGGGAGUACGUGUGCCGUGUGGUCGGCAGCUCAGGUACCCAGGAAGCCUCAGUCCUUGUCACCAUCCAGCAGCGCCUUAGUGGCUCCCACUCCCAGGGUGUGGCGUACCCCGUCCGCAUCGAGUCCUCCUCAGCCUCCCUGGCCAAUGGACACACCCUGGACCUCAACUGCCUGGUUGCCAGCCAGGCUCCCCACACCAUCACCUGGUAUAAGCGUGGAGGCAGCUUACCCAGCCGGCACCAGAUCGUGGGCUCCCGGCUGCGGAUCCCUCAGGUGACUCCGGCAGACUCGGGCGAGUACGUGUGUCACGUCAGUAACGGUGCAGGCUCCCGGGAGACCUCGCUCAUCGUCACCAUCCAGGGCAGCGGUUCCUCCCACGUGCCCAGCGUCUCCCCACCGAUCAGGAUCGAGUCGUCUUCCCCCACGGUGGUGGAAGGGCAGACCUUGGAUCUGAACUGCGUGGUCGCCAGGCAGCCCCAGGCUAUCAUCACAUGGUACAAGCGUGGGGGCAGCCUUCCCUCCCGACACCAGACCCAUGGCUCCCACCUGCGGUUGCACCAAAUGUCUGUGGCUGACUCGGGCGAGUAUGUGUGCCGGGCCAACAACAACAUCGAUGCCCUGGAGGCCUCCAUCGUCAUCUCCGUCUCCCCUAGCGCCGGCAGCCCCUCCGCCCCUGGCAGCUCCAUGCCCAUCAGAAUUGAGUCAUCCUCCUCACACGUGGCCGAAGGGGAGACCCUGGAUCUGAACUGCGUGGUCCCCGGGCAGGCCCAUGCCCAGGUCACUUGGCACAAGCGUGGGGGCAGCCUCCCCAGUCACCAUCAGACCCGCGGCUCACGGCUGCGGCUGCACCAUGUGUCCCCGGCCGACUCGGGUGAAUACGUGUGCCGGGUGAUGGGCAGCUCUGGCCCCCUGGAGGCCUCAGUCCUGGUCACCAUCGAAGCCUCUGGCUCAAGUGCUGUCCACGUCCCCGCCCCAGGUGGAGCCCCACCCAUCCGCAUCGAGCCCUCCUCCUCCCGAGUGGCAGAAGGGCAGACCCUGGAUCUGAAGUGCGUGGUGCCCGGGCAGGCCCACGCCCAGGUCACGUGGCACAAGCGUGGAGGAAACCUCCCUGCCCGGCACCAGGUCCACGGCCCACUGCUGAGGCUGAACCAGGUGUCCCCGGCUGACUCUGGCGAGUACUCGUGCCAAGUGACCGGAAGCUCAGGCACCCUGGAGGCAUCUGUCCUGGUCACAAUUGAGCCCUCCAGCCCAGGACCCAUUCCUGCUCCAGGACUGGCCCAGCCCAUCUACAUCGAGGCCUCCUCUUCACACGUGACUGAAGGGCAGACUCUGGAUCUGAACUGUGUGGUGCCCGGGCAGGCCCAUGCCCAGGUCACGUGGUACAAGCGCGGGGGCAGCCUCCCCGCCCGGCACCAGACCCAUGGCUCCCAGCUGCGGCUCCACCUCGUCUCCCCUGCCGACUCAGGCGAGUAUGUGUGUCGUGCAGCCAGCGGCCCAGGCCCUGAGCAAGAAGCCUCCUUCACAGUCACCGUCCCGCCCAGUGAGGGGUCUUCCUACCGCCUUAGGAGCCCGGUCAUCUCCAUCGACCCGCCCAGCAGCACCGUGCAGCAGGGCCAGGAUGCCAGCUUCAAGUGCCUCAUCCAUGACGGGGCAGCCCCCAUCAGCCUCGAGUGGAAGACCCGGAACCAGGAGCUGGAGGACAACGUCCACAUCAGUCCCAAUGGCUCCAUCAUCACCAUCGUGGGCACCCGGCCCAGCAACCACGGUACCUACCGCUGCGUGGCCUCCAAUGCCUACGGUGUGGCCCAGAGUGUGGUGAACCUCAGUGUGCACGGGCCCCCUACAGUGUCCGUGCUCCCCGAGGGCCCCGUGUGGGUGAAAGUGGGAAAGGCUGUCACCCUGGAGUGUGUCAGUGCCGGGGAGCCCCGCUCCUCUGCUCGUUGGACCCGGAUCAGCAGCACCCCUGCCAAGUUGGAGCAGCGGACAUAUGGGCUCAUGGACAGCCACGCGGUGCUGCAGAUUUCAUCAGCUAAACCAUCAGAUGCGGGCACUUAUGUGUGCCUUGCUCAGAAUGCACUAGGCACAGCACAGAAGCAGGUGGAGGUGAUCGUGGACACGGGCGCCAUGGCCCCAGGGGCCCCUCAGGUCCAAGCUGAAGAAGCUGAGCUGACUGUGGAGGCUGGACACACGGCCACCUUGCGCUGCUCAGCCACAGGCAGCCCCGCGCCCACCAUCCACUGGUCCAAGCUGCGUUCCCCACUGCCCUGGCAGCACCGGCUGGAAGGUGACACACUCAUCAUACCCCGGGUAGCCCAGCAGGACUCGGGCCAGUACAUCUGCAAUGCCACUAGCCCUGCUGGGCACGCUGAGGCCACCAUCAUCCUGCACGUGGAGAGCCCACCAUAUGCCACCACGGUCCCAGAGCACGCUUCGGUGCAGGCAGGGGAGACGGUGCAGCUCCAGUGCCUGGCUCACGGGACACCCCCACUCACCUUCCAGUGGAGCCGCGUGGGCAGCAGCCUUCCUGGGAGGGCGACCGCCAGGAACGAGCUGCUGCACUUUGAGCGUGCAGCCCCUGAGGACUCAGGCCGCUACCGCUGCCGGGUCACCAACAAGGUGGGCUCAGCCGAGGCCUUUGCCCAGCUGCUCGUCCAAGGCCCUCCCGGCUCUCUCCCUGCCACCUCCAUCCCAGCAGGGUCCACGCCCACCGUGCAGGUCACGCCUCAGCUAGAGACCAAGAGCAUUGGGGCCAGCGUUGAGUUCCACUGUGCUGUGCCCAGCGACCGGGGUACCCAGCUCCGUUGGUUCAAGGAAGGGGGUCAGCUGCCUCCGGGUCACAGCGUGCAGGAUGGGGUGCUCCGAAUCCAGAACUUGGACCAGAGCUGCCAAGGGACGUAUAUAUGCCAGGCCCAUGGACCUUGGGGGAAGGCCCAGGCCAGUGCCCAGCUGGUUAUCCAAGCCCUGCCCUCGGUGCUCAUCAACAUCCGGACCUCUGUGCAGACCGUGGUGGUUGGCCACGCCGUGGAGUUCGAAUGCCUGGCACUGGGUGACCCCAAGCCUCAGGUGACAUGGAGCAAAGUUGGAGGGCACCUGCGGCCAGGCAUUGUGCAGAGCGGAGGUGUCGUCAGGAUCGCCCACGUAGAGCUGGCUGAUGCGGGACAGUAUCGCUGCACUGCCACCAACGCAGCUGGCACCACACAAUCCCACGUCCUGCUGCUUGUGCAAGCCUUGCCCCAGAUCUCAAUGCCCCAAGAAGUCCGUGUGCCUGCUGGUUCUGCAGCUGUCUUCCCCUGCAUAGCCUCAGGCUACCCCACUCCUGACAUCAGCUGGAGCAAGCUGGAUGGCAGCCUGCCACCUGACAGCCGCCUGGAGAACAACAUGCUGAUGCUGCCCUCAGUCCGACCCCAGGACGCAGGUACCUACGUCUGCACCGCCACUAACCGCCAGGGCAAGGUCAAAGCCUUUGCCCACCUGCAGGUGCCAGAGCGGGUGGUGCCCUACUUCACGCAGACCCCCUACUCCUUCCUACCGCUGCCCACCAUCAAGGAUGCCUACAGGAAGUUCGAGAUCAAGAUCACCUUCCGGCCCGACUCAGCCGAUGGGAUGCUGCUGUACAAUGGGCAGAAGCGAGUCCCAGGGAGCCCCACCAACCUGGCCAACCGGCAGCCCGACUUCAUCUCCUUCGGCCUCGUGGGGGGAAGGCCCGAGUUCCGGUUCGAUGCAGGCUCAGGCAUGGCCACCAUCCGCCAUCCCACACCACUGGCCCUGGGCCAUUUCCACACCGUGACCCUGCUGCGCAGCCUCACCCAGGGCUCCCUGAUUGUGGGUGACCUGGCCCCGGUCAAUGGGACCUCCCAGGGCAAGUUCCAGGGCCUGGAUCUGAACGAGGAACUCUACCUGGGUGGCUAUCCUGACUAUGGUGCCAUCCCCAAGGCGGGGCUGAGCAGCGGCUUCAUAGGCUGUGUCCGGGAGCUGCGCAUCCAGGGCGAGGAGAUCGUCUUCCAUGACCUCAACCUCACGGCGCACGGCAUCUCCCACUGCCCCACCUGUCGGGACCGGCCCUGCCAGAAUGGCGGUCAGUGCCAUGACUCUGAGAGCAGCAGCUACGUGUGCGUCUGCCCAGCUGGCUUCACCGGGAGCCGCUGUGAGCACUCGCAGGCCCUGCACUGCCAUCCAGAGGCCUGUGGGCCCGACGCCACCUGUGUGAACCGGCCUGACGGUCGAGGCUACACCUGCCGCUGCCACCUGGGCCGCUCGGGGUUGCGGUGUGAGGAAGGUGUGACAGUGACCACCCCCUCGCUGUCGGGUGCUGGCUCCUACCUGGCACUGCCCGCCCUCACCAACACACACCACGAGCUACGCCUGGACGUGGAGUUCAAGCCACUCGCCCCUGACGGGGUCCUGCUGUUCAGCGGGGGGAAGAGCGGGCCUGUGGAGGACUUCGUGUCCCUGGCGAUGGUGGGCGGCCACCUGGAGUUCCGCUAUGAGUUGGGGUCAGGGCUGGCCGUUCUGCGGAGCGCCGAGCCGCUGGCCCUGGGCCGCUGGCACCGUGUGUCUGCAGAGCGUCUCAACAAGGACGGCAGCCUGCGGGUGAAUGGUGGACGCCCUGUGCUGCGCUCCUCGCCCGGCAAGAGCCAGGGCCUCAACCUGCACACCCUGCUCUACCUGGGGGGUGUGGAGCCUUCCGUGCCACUGUCCCCGGCCACCAACAUGAGCGCUCACUUCCGCGGCUGUGUGGGCGAGGUGUCAGUGAAUGGCAAACGGCUGGACCUCACCUACAGUUUCCUAGGCAGCCAGGGCAUCGGGCAAUGCUAUGAUAGCUCCCCAUGUGAGCGCCAGCCUUGCCAACAUGGUGCCACGUGCAUGCCCGCUGGCGAGUAUGAGUUCCAGUGCCUGUGUCGAGAUGGAUUCAAAGGAGACCUGUGUGAGCACGAGGAGAACCCCUGCCAGCUCCGUGAACCCUGUCUGCAUGGGGGCACCUGCCAGGGCACCCGCUGCCUCUGCCUCCCUGGCUUCUCUGGCCCACGCUGCCAACAAGGCUCUGGACAUGGCAUAGCAGAGUCCGACUGGCAUCUUGAAGGCAGCGGGGGCAAUGAUGCCCCUGGGCAGUACGGAGCCUAUUUCCACGAUGAUGGCUUCCUCGCCUUCCCUGGCCAUGUCUUCUCCAGGAGCCUGCCCGAGGUGCCCGAGACCAUCGAGCUGGAGGUUCGGACCAGCACAGCCAGUGGCCUCCUGCUCUGGCAGGGUGUGGAGGUGGGAGAGGCCGGCCAAGGCAAGGACUUCAUCAGCCUCGGGCUUCAAGACGGGCACCUUGUCUUCAGGUACCAGCUGGGUAGUGGGGAGGCCCGCCUGGUCUCUGAGGACCCCAUCAAUGACGGCGAGUGGCACCGGGUGACAGCACUGCGGGAGGGCCGCAGAGGUUCCAUCCAAGUCGACGGUGAGGAGCUGGUCAGCGGCCGGUCCCCAGGUCCCAACGUGGCAGUCAACGCCAAGGGCAGCGUCUACAUCGGCGGAGCCCCUGACGUGGCCACGCUGACCGGGGGCAGAUUCUCCUCAGGCAUCACAGGCUGUGUCAAGAACCUGGUGCUGCACUCGGCCCGACCCGGCGCCCCGCCCCCACAGCCCCUGGACCUGCAGCACCGCGCCCAGGCCGGGGCCAACACACGCCCCUGCCCCUCGUAGGCACCUGCCUGCCCCACACGGACUCCCGGGCCACGCCCCAGCCCGACAAUGUCGAGUAUAUUAUUAUUAAUAUUAUUAUGAAUUUUUGUAAGAAACCGAGGCGAUGCCACGCUUUGCUGCUACCGCCCUGGGCUGGACUGGAGGUGGGCAUGCCACCCUCACACACACAGCUGGGCAAAGCCACAAGGCUGGCCAGCAAGGCAGGUUGGAUGGGAGUGGGCACCUCAGAAAGUCACCAGGACUUGGGGUCAGGAACAGUGGCUGGGUGGGCCCAGAACUGCCCCCACUGUCCCCCUACCCACCGAUGGAGCCCCCAGAUAGAGCUGGGUGGCCUGUUUCUGCAGCCCUUGGGCAGUUCUCACUCCUAGGAGAGCCAACCUCGGCUUGUGGGCUGGUGCCCCACAGCUACCUGAGACGGGCAUCGCAGGAGUCUCUGCCACCCACUCAGGAUUGGGAAUUGUCUUUAGUGCCGGCUGUGGAGCAAAAGGCAGCUCACCCCUGGGCAGGCGGUCCCCAUCCCCACCAGCUCGUUUUUCAGCACCCCCACCCACCUCCACCCAGCCCCUGGCACCUCCUCUGGCAGACUCCCCCUCCUACCACGUCCUCCUGGCCUGCAUUCCCACCCCCUCCUGCCAGCACACAGCCUGGGGUCCCUCCCUCAGGGGCUGUAAGGGAAGGCCCACCCCAACUCUUACCAGGAGCUGCUACAGGCAGAGCCCAGCACUGAUAGGGCCCCGCCCACCGGGCCCCGCCCACCCCAGGCCACAUCCCCACCCAUCUGGAAGUGAAGGCCCAGGGACUCCUCCAACAGACAACGGACGGACGGAUGCCGCUGGUGCUCAGGAAGAGCUAGUGCCUUAGGUGGGGGAAGGCAGGACUCACGACUGAGAGAGAGAGGAGGGGGAUAUGACCACCCUGCCCCAUCUGCAGGAGCCUGAAGAUCCAGCUCAAGUGCCAUCCUGCCAGUGGCCCCCAGACUGUGGGGUUGGGACGCCUGGCCUCUGUGUCCUAGAAGGGACCCUCCUGUGGUCUUUGUCUUGAUUUUUCUUAAUAAACGGUGCUAUCCCCGCCA